AGCCACCAUGCCUGGCCCACAUUUUAGAAUAUUAUAAAGUAUAAGGGUUUGUUUUUUUCCCUCCAGAUAACCAAAAUGUCCAUAUGUAAUUAUCAGAGGAACCUGCCCCCAAUAUUUCAAUGUAGGUUCUUUCUAUUUUUCCUAAGUGUCGGCUGGUCUGAGAAAUAAAGAGAAAGAGUACAAAGAGAGGAAUUUUACAGCUGGGCCGCCGGGGGUGACAUCACAUAUCGGUAGGACUGUGAUGCCCACCUGAGCCACAAAACCAGCAAGUUUUUAUUAAGGAUUUCAAAAGGGGAGGAAUGUACGAACAGGGAGUAGGUCACAUGCUUUAAAGGGCAAAAAGCAGAGCAAAGAUCACAUGCUUCUGAGGAAACAGGGCAAGGACAAAAUCAGAACUCCUGAUAAGGGUCUAUGUUCAGCAGUGCACGUAUUGUCUUGAUAAACAUCUUAACAGAAAACGGUUCGAGAGCAGAGAACCAGUCUGACCUCAAAUUUACCAGGGCUGGGGUUUCCCAAUCCUAGUAAGCCUGAGGGUACUGCAGGAGACCAGGGUGUAUCUCAGUCCUUAUCUCAACCGCAUAGGACAGACACUCCCAUAGGACAGACACUCCCAGAGUGGCCAUUUAUAGACCUCCCCCCAGGAAUGCAAUUCUUUCCCUAGGGUCUUAAUAUUCCUUGCUAGGAAAAGAAUUUAGCAAUAUCUCUCCUACUUGCACGUCUGUUUAUAGGCUCUCUGCAAGAAGAAAAAUAUGGCUCUUUUUGCCUGACCCCGCAGGCAGUCAGACCUUAUGGUCGUCUUCCCUUGUUCGCUAAAAUUGCUGUUAUUCUGUUCUUUUUCAAGGUGCACUGAUUUCAUAUUGUUCAAACACAUGUUUUACAAUCAAUUUGUACAGUUAAUGCAAUCAUCACAGUGGUCCAGAGGUGACGUACAUCCUCAGUUUAUGAAGAUAAUAGGAUUAAGAGAUUAAAAUAAAGACAGGCAUAAGAAAUUAUGAAAGCAUUAUUUGGGAAGUGAUAAAUGUCCAUGAAAUCUUCACAAUUUAUGUUCCUCUGCCAUGGCUCCAGCUGGUCCCUCCAUUUGGGGUCCCUGACUUCCCGCAACAUGUAAUAGUUCCUAAAACAUCUUCUACCAUUGUCUCAGUUACUUCUCUUGUGUCAACCAGAGUCGUGGAGACUGAAAAUCCAAGCAAAAAGGUUUAUUGGUGGUUUUAGAAUUGAAUUCAAGGAACACAGAUUCCAGAGGCAUCUGAAAUCAUGUCCUAACUAUUUAAUUCAUAUGUCCUAAGAGAUAUAUGAGGUCUUUUAAAGAGAAAGGUGGGAGAGGGUUAUCAAACAAUUCAUUAGUUAGAAUAAGGGUUUCUAGGCAGAAGUCCUUGAUUCAGGGGUUUGGAAAAAGUUCAGUCAUCAGCAUAGCAUAGUCUUUUCAGAAGUGGCAGCAAUUUCAUCUGCAGCAUCAGCAAGUACGUUCUACAGUCAAGCAGUUGCAGAAUGACAUUCAGGAACAAAAUGGUGUUGUUCUGGUCAGCUCCCAUUAGCCUUCCAUACACACUUGUCUUCAUGGUACCUGUACCCUUGACCUCCGUGUUUUCAAAAAGUUUAAAACUUUUUGAUCAAGACUCACAAUAAGAAAUAUACGUUACAUUGUGACUGUAGUACACAAACCACACUUAGGUGUAACAGUAUAAUGUAUAGUACAUUUUGGUCUUUUCUAUUUAAUUUUAUUCUAUUUAGUCUUAUUUUACUGAAAAAAUAUUGAUCACAGUCUGCUAAACUGAUUUUGUAAUCCAUUCAUGGAUAAUGACCAGUAGUUAAAAAAUCACUCUUCUCAUCUAUACUGUUCUUUUUUCAACUGCUAUAUUUUUCAUAUUUAAUAUUUCCAAUUCACCUUUUUAUGGUUUCGUUUUAUCUUAUUAAUCUUUUCUUAUUUCUUUUAGCAUAUUAUUAUGCUUAUUAAUAUAUUUGGCCUCUCUGUUCUAAUUCCUCUGCUCCUGAUGGAAUCAGUAAUCUUUGUUUUUCUUUUGAAAUAGUGGUGCUCUCUAGAUGUCUUGUUUUGGCCUGUGAACAUAUCUCUGUAUACUCUCUGGUAGUGGUAAGAGUAAAGGAGGCCAGACCCAAGUCUGUUUCGGCCCUACUAAGCUGACAUAGGGGGUGGAGGCCUGGAGAGGGGCUGGAGUGAUGAGCUCCAAGGCAGAGAGCCCCAAGCACUAGAAAAAGAUGGUUAAUCACUCUUUGUUCUGCUAAACAGCCCGUGAGAUUAGGGCUUAACCUUCAGCCUCUGAUUUUAAAGGUUAUUAAAUAGCAGAGUAGAUAAUUUCCUUCGAUACUACUCCUGUGUUAUCUUUUGUAUUUUUGCUAUUUGUGUUUCAAAAAGUGAAAAUGCUAGUUAGUAGUUUCUACACUACUUACAUUUAAAUAUUGUCUUUGGGUUUGCAGCCACCACCACUCUGCAGCCAUCACCAUCUAGUCUGCAGAGACUAGAACUGCCAAUUGCUGUUGGGGGUGAGCGGCAUCUAUCCAGGCUGGUGGGAUGGUGGUAAAAGAAUUUACCAAGACAGUUGUAGGUAAAGAAAGGCAGAUUUUUUUUUUUUUUUUUUUUUUUUUGAGACGGAGUCUUGCUGUUUCACCCAGGCUGGAGCGCAGUGGCAUGAUCUUGGCUCACUGCAACCUCUGCCUCCCAGGUUCACGCCAUUCUCCUGCCUCAGCCUCCUGAGUAGCUGGGACUACAGGCGCCCGCCACCACACCCAGCUAAUUUUUUGUAUUUUUAGUAGAGACGGGGUUUCACCAUGUUAGCCAGGAUGGUCUCGAUCUCCUGACCUUGUGAUCUGCCCGCCUCAGCCUCCCAAAGUGCUGGGAUUACAGGCGUGAGCCACCGCGCCCGGCCAAGAAAGGCAGAUUUAUUAGAGAAAAUAUGAAAAUACAUUGCAAGGGAGCAACGGGCAGAACCAGCAAGAGAGGACCCAACUGCCAGGAGACAAAGGCUUGCUGGGGAUUUUAUAGAAUGGAACUUGGGCUGAUUGACAGCACCAAGGUAGGAGGGAACUAACUUGCAUCCUUCUGUCAGCCGAGGUGUUUGAUGAUAGAUCAAAGUGUUUGGUGAUAAGCAGGAGGUUUAUGAGUUUUGUAUGUUGUCUGCACAGGAGGGCUAUAUGUUCUGGGCCAUAAAGAAAGGCAGACCUAUAGCUUAUCUGCUUCUUCUUUUUGUUUAUAUGUUCUGGACCAUGAAGAAAGGCAGACCUGUAGCUUAUUUGCUUUCCCCUUGUCCUGCCAGCCUGACUCCUUUUCCCUAAUUAGGACUCCACAAUUGCUCUGACUUCACUUCACCUUCUGCCUAAAGCCUGUAAUCAAAAGGAAGCAAGGUCUGAUGAUAGCACUCCAGCAUAUGUUUUUCUGUGGUUUUUGCUUGUUUGUUGUUUUUUUUUUGAGACAGGGUCUCACUCUGUCACCCAGGGUAGAGUGCAUAAUCAUGGCUCACUGCAGCCUCAACCUCCUGGGCUCAGGUGAUCCUCCCACCUCAGCCUCCUGAGUAGCUAGGACUACAGGCACCCACUACCACAUCCAGCUAAUUUUUGUAUUUUUUUUAGAGACAGGGUUUCACCAUGUUGCCCAGGCUGGUCUUGAACCUCUGGGCUCAAGCAAUCUGCCCACCUUGGCCUCCCAAAGAUCUAGGAUUAUAAGUGUGAGCCACAGUGCCCAGCCUACAUGCUAGAGCAUGUGACUAACCCUGUGACUUUACAUUGGAAUUGCACUUUAACCUGUUUUUAAUGUUUCUUCUGCAUUAACCUGAUAUAUCUUUAUUAUAAUGCUUUAUUUUCUUCAUGUUAGCUUGCAUUUGAACAUAGAUACCUUAGUGGUGUAGUUUGCUUGGCUCUGUGGAAGUAGAAUAAUAUCUCCACGUUCUUAUUGUUGAUGGUUCUGUUGAAGUAUGUAAUGUUAUAUGUGACUCAUAGAUGAACCAUAAUGACACUGUAGAAAAAUGGUGGUUUUCUUCACUUUUCCACCAUCCACAUUUCUUACUAUCCCUUUAGCUUAUCCUUCAGUGACUUAGGUUUUUGUUUGAUGGCAAUCCUUACCAUUUUUUAAGCCUAAUUUUAGCUGAAUUUAAAAGGAGGGGUGAAGAGGGUGAAUGAGAUAGAAAAACAAGACAUGAUUUUUCUGGGUACUCUCCCUCUAGUCUCCAUCCUUAACAAGAGUCUUGCUUAUGACAUUAUUCAAAAAGCCAGAUACAACAUCCAUUACAAAGUGACACACAUCUUUGGAUGGCUGUUUUUGAAGUAUUUCAUAAAUCUUUUUAUACUCUCUGGAUGGAGAAGGCCUUUUUAAACAUGAUACUAAAGUUGGAAACCAAGAAAAAAAGUUGGAUGGAUUUGAUUACAUAAAAAUACAGACUUCCUUAUGGCAAGAAGAAAAAAAAAAAAGAAACAAAGUCAAAAACUUGGAAAAAUAUUUACAGUAUGUAUGAAAAUCUAGGGGCUUUUUUAUCUUGACAAUAUAAAGAAUCCCUCCAAGCCAAUAAGAAAAAACAAAACAACCAAAUAAAAAACCAGAAGAAUCAGGAAAUACUCAGAGGAAAAAAUACAAAUCUCCAAUAACAUAUCAAAGGAUAUUUAACCUUACUAGUCAUCAAAGUGACAGUUUGCCUUUCAGUUUGGCAGAGACUUUAAAAAAAUCCCAAAACCCAAUGUUAGCAAUAGUGUGGAGAAACUGUCACUUUUAUCUCCUGCUAGUGAGAGUGUAAAUUGAUUUAAAAAAACCUUUUAGACGGACAGUUUGGCAUUAUUAAAAAUUCUAAAGAUUUGCUUAUUAUUAAUUCAACAAUUUACUUCCUGUAGAAAUCUCAGGAAGAUAAUAGAAAAGUACACACAUAUAUUCAUUAUAAUAUCAUUUAUGAUAAUAAGCAUAGUUAUAUAUAGCAUAUGUUAUAAGCAAGACACCUUUAUUUCUCACAACAUAUCCUGUUUUAGUAAUAAGGCUAGUAAAGCACAGAGAGAAAACUGAGCUUGAUGGCAAUCAUAGGGUUCCAGGUUGGGCAGUCUGCUUGCAAAGCACAUGUUCUUAAUCACGGCAUAAUAUUGCCUACCUAAAGCAACCUAAAUGUUCAACUCAAGUGUUUGCCAGUGUAGGAUGCAUUUAAUAAGUUAUGAUACUUGCAGAAAAUGGAAUAAUAUACAACCACAAUCUAUUGAUUUUAUAAAAAGUGCUCAUCUUAUAUGUGAUCUGAUCCUGUUGUUCUUCAAAGCGUUUUUUAAACUCAAAAAACAUCAAAAUGAAUAUAUACAGCCAUAAAAUCAUGUCCUUUACAGCAACAUGGAUGCAGCUGGAGGCCGUUAUCCUAAUGAAUAAAUGCAGACACAGAAAACCAAAUACUGCAUGUUCUCACUUAUAAGUGGGAGCCAAUCGCUGGGUGCACACAGACAUAAAGAUGGGAAAAAUACACACUGGGGACUUCAAAAGGGAGGAAGGAGGAAGGGAAGCAAGGAUUGAAAAACUACCUGUCAAGUACUGUGUUCACUCUUUGGGUGAUGGGUUCAAUUGAAGCCUAAACUUCAGCAUCAUGCAGUAUAUCCCUGUAACUAACCUGCACAUGUACCCCCUGAAUCUAACAGUUUUAAAAAGCUAAUAUAAUUUUAUCUCUGGGUAUUGGUAUUAUGGGUAAUUUUAGUUAUAGAGGUUAAAAGGUUAGGCUUUGGAAUUAAAAGGACCUGGGUUCCAAUCCCAGCUCCACUCCUUUUGGCUAUGUUCUUUAUGUUGGCUACUUAAGCUCUCAGGGUCUUAAUUCCCGAUUUGUAAAAUGGCAAUGACCAAUCCCUUGGGGGCGGGCAGUGGGGUGGUGGGCAGUGGAAAGAGAGAGAGAGAGAAUAUUAAAUAACAUAAUGUAGGCCAGGCACAGUGGCUCACGCCUGUAAUCCCAGCACUUUGGGAGGCCAAGGCGGGCAGAUCACCUGAAGCCGGGAGUUUGAGACCAGCCUGACCAACAUGGAGAAACCACAUCUCUACUAAAAAAUACAAAAUUAGCCAGGCGUGGUGGUGCAUGCCUGUAAUCCCAGCUACUGGGAGGCUGAGGCAGGAGAAUCGCUUGAACCCGGGAGGCGGAGGUUGCAGUGAGCCGAGAUCACGCCAUUGCACUCCAGCCUGGGCAACAAGAGUGAAAUUCCAUCUCAAAAAUAAAAUAAAAUAAAAAAUAAUAUAAUGUAUAUGACAGUACCCUUCCUGAUUUUACAUCCUGAAGUCCAAACUCUAGAUCUACGGAGCUGCGAUAUAUCAGAUGCUGCUCUCCUGCACCUGUCUAACUGUAGAAAACUGAAGAAAUUAAAUUUAAAUGCUUCAAAAGGGAACCGAGUUUCUGUAACUUCAGAAGGAAUAAAAGCUGUGGCUUCAUCUUGUUCAUACCUACACGAAGCUUCUUUGAAAAGAUGCUGCAAUCUCACUGACGAAGGAGUCGUUGCUCUUGCACUCAAUUGCCAGCUGCUAAAGAUCAUCGAUUUAGGUGGCUGCUUAAGUAUUACUGAUGUGUCCUUACAUGCAUUAGGAAAAAACUGCCCAUUUUUGCAGUGUGUCGACUUUUCAGCUACUCAGGUAUCUGACAGUGGUGUGAUUGCACUUGUUAGUGGACCUUGUGCGAAGAAAUUAGAGGAGAUUCAUAUGGGACAUUGUGUAAAUCUGACUGAUGGGGCUGUCGAAGCUGUCCUUACUUACUGUCCUCAAAUACGUAUAUUACUCUUCCAUGGAUGCCCCUUGAUAACAGAUCAUUCCCGAGAAGUGUUGGAGCAAUUAGUAGGCCCAAACAAACUAAAGCAAGUGACAUGGACUGUUUAUUGAUGCUUUUUUGAAGAUGAUCAAUGCUAGGAAAGCUUAUCAAAACUACUUUCCCAGGAAACCAUCUAUAGAGAUUUGCAUUCUACUUAAUGUUAACACUAUUUUUAAUUAUUUUAUUGUCUUAAGUUAUAACUCUCAGAGAAUUAGCUAAGUCUUGGUAUAUACAUGGUUUGUGCUUUACUCUUAAACAUCUUUAAAGUGCUAUUAUUCUAUAUCUGUUGGAUGAGUCAUUAUUUUUGAAAUGAUAAUCCUAGCAUGAACUCUGAUCUAUGGUGUUGGAUUCUGUUUCUUAAAUAACUUUAAAAUUAACUGUUUUCCCUUGAGAUUUCCUUCUCCUAUGUAGGUAUUUGAGCUAUUGUUCUAAGUUUACCUGUAAGUAUAAACCUUGGGAGAAUCUAAGUAAACAUAUUUCUAAAAGCAUAGUUACCUUCCUAUUUUCUGGCUCUUACCUUCUUGGAGUAUUUAAAUGCCCAUUUGCCAAAAGCAGACCUGAACAUCAAGCCUGUUAAUUCUUCAAAGAAUUUAGGUAUUUGUUUCACCGAAAUGAAGUGACUUAUUAGCCAUUCAGCGUAUUAGUAUUACAGAGGCUCUUGCCCAGCCACAUCCAUUCAUUGAUUUUUAUGGCUACUCUUCCCAGUUACAUUUUAUGCAUCUGUAAGCUUUCCUUCCUUAGCAAAAUUGCAUUCAAAAAUGUGUAAAAAUGAGUAAAUACAGAAUAUCACUACAGAGACUUGUAUCCUCAGGUUUAUUGAUUUCACAUUGUGAAAUAAACAGCAAAGGUCUUAGUUUUCAAGUGAAAACUUUUUGGUAAUCACAAAAUUACCUGACACAUACCACGCUUAAACCAACCCCCAAAUUUAGCAUAUUCAUUUUGCCAUGAGCCAGUCUUGAGAUUUUCUUAAAAGAUUUCUUAUUUUGCCUCUGAUGUAGUGAAAAACGGGGUAAGUAUGCUAACUUUCUUGUAUAUGUUGGGGGGUACUUAUUCAACUCCAUUUCUUGUCCUUACAAGAUUUAUAAAUGUGGUAUGUUUAUAGUGUGGAUAUAUAUGUUGCCACUGCAAAGGUGGUGCAUAUGUAUAUAUGUGCAAAAUGGGUAAGGCCUGUUCUAACUAUGAAAUUUUUCUAAAGACAAAUUCAAUAAAAUUUAAUACUGAAUAUUUAACCAAGUCAA